CUUUUUGUGUCCUGUUUGCUAAAGGCAUGCGGGCUACAGCAUUCAAGAGAGGGAGUCGUUAACAAAGGGAAAGAGAUAAAUGUAAAUAAGCUCACAUUUACAGAAUGAGCGGUUUGCAGUAAAAAGCUGCGGCAGCCCAGAGUCUGCUACUUUAGGCUGGGCUAACCUUUCCCUGUAAAAAAAAAAAAAAAAAAAAAAAAAAAAAAAUGGAUAAAAAUAUGCACUUCCAAAGGGCGAGUUGCCCAUUUACAUGUUUAUUAGCUAAUUAUCUACAGGCAUCAGCACAUUCUCUCAUCUAGCACACUCUUUCUUGGGAACAAAAUUCCCAACAUCAUAUCCCAUCAACAUAGAUUAUAAAACCUUUUGCCUUGUCACAGAUGAAAAGUUGCACUCUUGCCAAGAAGGAUGAGUUCACCUGAUAAACUUGAUGGCAUCUACAUUCUAAAGUCUCUCCUGCCAAUCAGAGAUGGGAAUGAAAGCCUUAUUGGAACAAUCAGGCCAGUCUUUCAGAAUGUGUGCUCUCUGCAAGUUAAAGGGAGAACCAGGAAGAUGCCUCACAGAAACAUUCAGGCCAAGCUUAGCUAAAGCUUGAUCUAUUCAAUUGCCUUUUGGGAAAAUGCAGUGAGAAUUGUUGCCCUUGCUGUGGUUUGUUCAGCGCCUAAUUGUGUAGCUACCUUUUGUCUGUGUAUAUGGUCAUCACAUAUAGUCUGCCCUUGGCCUUCUUGUUGGGGGAAGAACAAAACCUGUAAUGUGUUUGCGAAUAUUAGUACUGAAAAUUGGGAGCCCAAUAAAAGGUUACCUACCACUGGGAAUCCACCUUUACUUUAAGCGGAUAAAUAAUCAGUUAUCAGAACAAUGUAACGGGUAAAUGAUCUAAUGAUUCUACAUGGUUAUGUCCUGAAAUAUGCCGAUAACCUCAUAUUCUGAGGGGUGAAGUGACCAGGAAACAGGUGGGAAGGGUUGAGGGUUGAGACCUAAACAAUUAGAGGUGAUAUGCCUGCUGAAAUGAGCACAAGGACAGAGGAUGAGGAAAAUAAGGGAAUUUGGAAGACUUUAGGAUAUUAGUGGCAUCUUUCUCUGUGAUUCUUAGCUUCCGGUAUUAAUUAAUACUAUUUAUUUCUAAUAUUCAAAUAAAUCUAGCAAUCAUUUCAUUAAGUCUAAUAAAAAUUAAUGACCCUCCUUGCUUGCAGACUUUGAGGAAAUAAAAAAUGUUUUACAGUGGCCAAUGUAAGCAGGUGAAAAUAAAUGAUGGAAAAGAACAGCCAGUAAGGCCACCAGCAUGGCACUCAUUGAAGGUUGCUUUUCUGUCAGUCAAGACUGAAGAUUAAAGGAGAAGAGAAACUGAGACUCAGAAAUGGACUGUGACUUGCUCUCACAGAGCUCGUGAUGGGGCUGGAUGUGUCUAUAUUUAAUUAAUAUCAGUUAUAAAAACUUCUGGGUAUUUGAACUUCCUAAUUUGCUUGGAUUUUGAAUAAAAGGUUUUUUGUAUAAUCGUUAUCAACUGUGAAAGGCAUAAAAUAAUGUUAAUGCUUCUGUUUUCCUUUACGAUAAACCAAUAAAAUGGAAUAAAAUAUUCAUUUCAUUCCAGGAAGACAGAUUUCUGGAGGAGUGUGAAAAUCAACUCUCCUUAAUAUUAAGGACCCUGCCCAAUGGUAACAGUUGUUGCCAAGAAAAGAAAAAAAGAAAAAAAAAAGACCCAAUCACCCAUUGGAGGAAAUCUCUAACUACAGUGCCUCCAGGAAACUCAUUGGUUAUUCCAGUCUUAGAUAAAAUUGGUGCCAGGAUUUGGUUCGAACUAAUGUGGAGGAAAAUAUUUCCUACCGGUCCAUAGUGUCAGAGUGGUGAACCCCUGCAGCCAGCAGGCCUCCUGAAAAAAAAGUCCAUGGGUGACAGAAGAUUCAUUGACUUCCAAUUCCAAGAUUCAAAUUCAAGCCUCAGACCCAGGUUGGGCAAUGCUACUGCCAAUAAUACUUGCAUUGUUGAUGAUUCCUUCAAGUAUAAUCUCAAUGGUGCUGUCUACAGUGUUGUAUUCAUCUUGGGUCUGAUAACCAACAGUGUCUCUCUGUUUGUCUUCUGUUUCCGCAUGAAAAUGAGAAGUGAGACUGCUAUUUUUAUCACCAAUCUAGCUGUCUCUGAUUUGCUUUUUGUCUGUACACUACCUUUUAAAAUAUUUUACAACUUCAACCGCCACUGGCCUUUUGGUGACACCCUCUGCAAGAUCUCUGGAACUGCAUUCCUUACCAACAUCUAUGGGAGCAUGCUCUUUCUCACCUGUAUUAGUGUGGAUCGUUUCCUGGCCAUUGUCUAUCCUUUUCGAUCUCGUACUAUUAGGACUAGGAGGAAUUCUGCCAUUGUGUGUGCUGGUGUCUGGAUCCUAGUCCUCAGUGGCGGUAUUUCAGCCUCUUUGUUUUCCACCACUAAUGUCAACAAUGCAACCACCACCUGCUUUGAAGGCUUCUCCAAACGUGUCUGGAAGACUUAUUUAUCCAAGAUCACAAUAUUUAUUGAAGUUGUUGGGUUUAUCAUUCCUCUAAUAUUGAAUGUCUCUUGCUCUUCUGUGGUGCUGAGAACUCUUCGCAAGCCUGCUACUCUGUCUCAAAUUGGGACCAAUAAGAAAAAAGUACUGAAAAUGAUCACAGUACAUAUGGCAGUCUUUGUGGUAUGCUUUGUACCCUACAACUCUGUCCUCUUCUUGUAUGCCCUGGUGCGCUCCCAAGCUAUUACUAAUUGCUUUUUGGAAAGAUUUGCAAAGAUCAUGUACCCAAUCACCUUGUGCCUUGCAACUCUGAACUGUUGUUUUGACCCUUUCAUCUAUUACUUCACCCUUGAAUCCUUUCAGAAGUCCUUCUACAUCAAUGCCCACAUCAGAAUGGAGUCCCUGUUUAAGACUGAAACACCUUUGACCACAAAGCCUUCCCUUCCAGCUAUUCAAGAGGAAGUGAGUGAUCAAACAACAAAUAAUGGUGGUGAAUUAAUGCUAGAAUCCACCUUUUAGGUAUGAGAAAUGUGUUCAGGUCCAGAUAUGGUUUCUCCUAUAAUUUUUCCUAUGCUAUAAACUAAAGAUUUGAAGCUAAUGAUACUGAGAAUAAUGCACCAAAUCCAGUCAGAUACAUUUGUUUGAAGGUAUACUGUAGAGUUUUUAUUGCUGUUUUGUUCAGUAAUUAUAGGUCAAAUCUAAUUACAACAACCAAGAUGGAUUGCCAAACUCUUCUGCUUGGUUGGAAUUUCAUUGUAUCGCAUUAUCCAGGUGGCUAGUGGCAUUUGAUAAUAUAGAGAUGACUUUGAAACUUUCAAAAAGGUAUUUCUAUUCCAAUGAUAUUUGGUAAUUAGGUUGGGCCUAUAAAUAUAGAACAAAUUCAGGGAUUUUUAAAAAAUUGUGUUACUACUGAUAUAUGCUAGUUUUAUUUUAUUUUUUUGAACUGUCAUUGAGUUUAUUUUAGCACAAGAAUAUUUUUAGCCUAACAUUAUUAAUAAGAAAUGUGUCAAAUUUUUAACAUUGGUAAAAUAUGUUAUGUGCAUUUUGAAAACAGAAAACAAAUUGCGUUGGCAUGUACGUGGGUGGGAAGAAAAAGAAAAUUAACAGGAUUUACACAAUUAUAAUCACCAGCAGUGUGAGUUUAAAAAACUUCGUUGUUUUUACACCAAAUUAAAAUUUUCAUGUCAAACUUCAAAGCCAGAAAGCUGCUAAAUACGUGUCUGGCAGGUAAAAGCUGGAAAAUUACUUAAAACAGGAAAGUGUCAAUAAAAAAACUUGAGCAACACCAACAUAUUUUUUCUUAAAAUGUCACGUUAUCUUCAUUUUGGGAAACUAGGUUCUAUAAAAUAUUUAUCCUCCCUGUUAUACUUUGGAGCACAGCACAGCCAGAAAGGGGCUGCAUUUGUGCCCAGGUCAGGAGCAAAUUGAAAAAAAAAAUAAAGUAAUACAAAAAAAUCAAACUAUAAAGCAAAAACAUUUAUUAAAACCUGAAUUAAUCCUUUUUGGAGGGAGGAGUAGAGAUAUAUAACCUGAAAAUACUUAUUCUUUCUUAUCGAAUUUUGGAGCCUAAUAUAGCCAGGAGCUGCUGAAUUUGUGCCCCUGGAUUGGAAGCAAAUAAAAAAAAAAAACAACACAUAAACUAAACCAAACCAAAACAAAAAAACCAGAGAACCCCAAGAAAAAUAAAAAUAAAAAAACCUCAACAAUAAUUUGUAACACUUUCAUUACUAUUUGUUGAGGUUCUGUAAAUGUAAAAAUACUAUGUCAUUUGCAUAACAUUUUGAAGCACAACGCAGCUACCAAGUGGCUAAAUUCGUCUCCUGGUUAGGAACAAGUUGUGGGAAAAAAAGGUCAAAAAUCAAACUGCGAUAAAACAAACAAAACAAGCACAAACAAAAUUUAGAACUUGCAUUUUCUGAGCAUCUGCGAAACUUACAAAACACUAUAACAUUCAUAUAAUGCUUUGGAUCAAAUUGCAACUAAGAAGCUGCUAAAAUGGCACCCAGUUUAAAAGGAAUUAAAAACAGUAUUUUAAAAUCUACAAAAAAAGAGAAAAUUUUUUUAUAAUUUACUUAAACCGCAAAAAUCUUUAAAACUCUUACUAGUUUUUAAACUAAAGUGGAUAUUUAAGAAUAUUAGAACUUGUAAAUAUAACUUCUGAGCUUGAAAGAUGCUACAUUUGUGCUCAAGUCAGGAGCAGUGGAAAUAAACCCUCGUAUACACACAUACACAGCAGCAGCAACAACAAAAACCAAAAUUAAAUGUUAAACCCUGAAAAACAACAAAAAUAUUUUAAAAUGUGCAUUAAUCAAUUUUUAAAAUAUUUGGAUAACAUGGCAAUUUAAAAAUGCUAAGAAUUUUAAAACAAAACUUCCAGGAAAAAUGUAUCCUGCAAGUUGCUGAACUUGUGCCAGAAAGUGGUUAAACAAUUAUAAAGCACAGAACAAUAACAAAAAAGUAAAACUUCUAAAACAAUAAGCAAAUUUUUAAAACUCAUUAACUUGUUUUUCUUUCUGAUGAUAUGCAGACUUAAAAAUACUGAGACUUUUAAGUAAAAAUCUGUUAGCAUAAUGUAACUUUAAAAACUGUAAAAUCUGUGUCUGGGUUAGGAACAAAGUGAAAAAAUGCUAAAACAAUAGUAAAAACAAAUUCUUAAAACUGGCAUUACUUUUUCCCAAUGAAAGUCCUAAAAGUAAUUAUGCAUUAUGUAGUCUUAUGAAAAGAGGCUAUAGAUGGAAUAUAUAAGGCAUUAGAUUCAGUUAAAUAAAAUUAGGUUAAGAUAAGUUCAGUUGUUAGAUUAUAUGGUAAGAUCAAAUCAGUAAUAAAAGCGUGAAUAAUCUUUUGUUUCUUUCAGUAUUCAUGUUUUUCCAUUUCUUGUUAAGUAUAAAAUAUAUGUGAACAUUUGUUUGUGCCCUUGCUUCUUAACAUUAUAAAAUUUUAUGAUUAUGACACCAAACCAUUUAAUGGGAUAUUAACUAAGUUGAAAUAAAAUAUAUUAUUAAAUGUUUCUUGUGUAAUUUCCAUGUUUAGUUUUAAUUUUUUUAUAUUUCACUUCUCAAAUUUCCAUUUUUAUAGUUAAUAUAAAUUGCUAAUAAUAAAACUUGUCACAUUAACAAUGUAACCAAGAAAAUGUAAAGUAUAACUAAAUAUAAAAGUGACUAUGUUACAUCGAAAGGAAAAGCAAUUUUGCAGCUGUAAUUGCAACUUGGAUUUUAAAUGUUUAUUAAAUGUAAUAAAAUAUAUUUGAAUUA